ACUCUGGGGAAAGGAGGGUACAACCACAUGUAAAUUUUAUUAUAAUGAUGGUAUAAUGAACUUGGGGUGACCUGAGGGCAUGUUUUUGUGUUACUGGGCAUGUGCCCCUUUAGGAGACUUCCACCUGUGCCUUACUUUCUCUUUCUUUGGGAUGUGCUGGCCACAGACUUUACCAAAAACUCCAUCCAUUAGGAUGGCAUUAGGACGGUUCUGGGGCUAAACUUAGGUGGGCCAGGGGCUGUUUCACUGUCAGCCUUUCUACUCUCUUUUCUUACCCACUCCUAGCUGCUAAUGUCUAUUUAACUACCUAAUAUUUCCCCCUUUAGAGAAAAAAAGCCAAAUUUUUGGGUAGAUCGGUGACAAUUAAUCUGGCUACUUCCUGCUGACAAGAGGCAGUGGUAAUAAUUGGGUUCUCUUUUUUGCUCUCUUGUAGCUGGUAGGUUGGGCAGAGAAAAGUGGUGGCCAUCCAAGGGGCCCACGUAGAUAUCAGACAUGGUUGAGACCUCGCGGUAACCUUGUGUAGAAUCAUUUGGAGUUUUAUGGAUUCUAGGUGGGAAGAAACAAAACAACCUUGUAAAUCAAAUGAGCAUCGUUUGAAAGCUAUAAGUUGUAUAAAGCUGUUUUAGGACCAAGAAAGGGGGCUAACCAGGAAAACCAGGACCAGUUGUUAAAUUUCCACCAGUCAAAGCCUCCUGAAACUCUGUUUUCCAUUAACUUGUUGGCCCUGUCUGUAAUUUUUUUAAGUUGGUUUGCACUUUACCUGAUUGGUUGAUGAAAACAGCAAUGUUUAUCAAGUGUUGCACAAGCUCCCCCUUGAUUGGCUGUGAGCAAAUUAAAAGCUCAUCAAUUUCAUAAGACUAUGCUUGCUAAUGAAGCAAUUUGUUCUGAAAGGGUAUUGACCUGGUUAGUUAGAUUAAUAAUUUGUUGAGUAAUUUUUAAGAAGAGUUUCUGGGCAGUAAAAAUGGAGUUAAGGAGGUCCUCCAGUUCCCGUGCCAAUACCAGCCAGAACGCCAAUUAUAGUCAGUGCUGUUAAAACUCCUCUUUCAGUUUUACCAGAUUGAGCGUGUAUAGGGAGGGGAAUGCUAUCGAUAAGAGUGAGUUUGGGGAUGAUGUAAACUAGGGCCAAAUCCCCGUUUAAUUAGCAGACAAGCAGAGAUAUGCCUUGUUUCUAUACAAAAAUGUGAUUUGUCAUGUUAAGACAAAUAUCAACAGUGAUACUAAAGUAGGGUUUUUCCAUGCUGUGUAAGUCUGCUUUAAUACCCUCAGAAGUGGAAGUCAAGGCUAGUUCAUGUAAUGGGGGAACACAGGCAGUACUUGACAGAAUGAAAGAGGAAUCAAAAGCCCAAUUAGAGGAAGGAGUGAUGGGAUCCCAACCAAUAUUGUGAAAUUAUGGGGAGCUGCAGUUUUUUGCAAUGAUUUUGCCCGAAGUUGUGAGACUGAAACCAGAAGUUGUUAUGUUUAAAAUGAUAUUCUGGUGUGGGUCUGGGGAAAAGGGUAGAUCCAGAAUAGCUGGCUUCUUUCCACAUAGUGGUUCUGUUGGGGGGCUUGGGAAAUGAAUAAAACACAAAGAAGAAUUAGAAUAUCAGGUGAAGGUAGCAGGUGCUCCUGGCAGAAGAACCCACAUAAGGAAGUGUCCAGAAGCCACACAGGGUAUAUCUCAGAGCCUGGAGAACGUGUCUGGUUAUUAUGCAGAUGCACGGCUGGAGGUGGGAUCCACACAGCUCAGAACAGCUGGAUCUUGCUCACACUCUUUCAAGAGAAGCUUCCUUGAAAAGAAACGCUUUACUGAAGAGGCCACCAAAUACUUCCGGGAGAGAGUCAGCCCAGUGCAUCUGCAAAUCCUGCUGACUAACAAUGAAGCCUGGAAGAGAUUCGUGACUGCGGCUGAAUUGCCCAGGGAUGAGGCAGAUGCUCUCUACGAAGCUCUGAAGAAGCUUAGAACAUAUGCAGCUAUUGAGGACGAAUAUGUGCAGCAGAAAGAUGAGCAGUUUAGGGAAUGGUUUUUGAAAGAGUUUCCCCAAGUCAAGAGGAAGAUCCAGGAGUCCAUAGAAAAGCUUCGUGCCCUUGCAAAUGGUAUUGAAGAGGUCCACAGAGGCUGCACCAUCUCCAAUGUGGUGUCCAGCUCCACUGGCGCUGCCUCUGGCAUCAUGUCCCUUGCUGGUCUUGUUUUGGCACCAUUUACAGCAGGGACGAGUCUGGCCCUUACUGCAGCUGGGGUAGGGCUGGGAGCAGCGUCUGCUGUGACUGGGAUCACCACCAGCAUCGUGGAGCACUCAUACACAUCAUCAGCAGAAGCUGAAGCCAGCAGGCUGACUGCAACCAGCAUUGACCGAUUGAAGGUAUUUAAGGAAGUUAUGCGUGACAUCACACCCAACUUACUUUCCCUUCUUAAUAAUUAUUACGAAGCCACACAAACCAUUGGGAGUGAAAUCCGUGCCAUCAGGCAAGCCAGAGCCAGGGCCCGACUCCCUGUGACCACCUGGCGAAUCUCAGCUGGAAGUGGUGGUCAAGCAGAGAGAACGAUUGCAGGCACCACCCGGGCAGUGAGCAGAGGAGCCCGGAUCCUGAGUGCGACCACUUCAGGCAUCUUCCUUGCACUGGAUGUGGUCAACCUUGUAUACGAGUCAAAGCACUUGCAUGAGGGGGCAAAGUCUGCAUCUGCUGAGGAGCUGAGGCGGCAGGCUCAGGAGCUGGAGGAGAAUCUAAUGGAGCUCACUCAGAUCUAUCAGCGUCUGAAUCCAUGCCAUACCCACUGACCCCAGACCAGUGCAGCCAGCAGGGGAGGUGAGCCAUACACAGGCCACGACAAAAUGCAGGCAUUUUAUUAGGGGGAUAAAGAGGGCAAGGUAAAGUUUAUGGAGCUGAGUGUUAGUGACUUUGGCAUUUCUGUAGCUGAGCACAGCAGGGGAGGGGUUAAUGCAGAUGGCAAGUGCACCAAGGAGAAGGCAGGAAUGCUGGAGCCUGGAAUAAGGGAGGAGAGGGGACUGGAGAGUGUGGGGAAUAGGAAGAAGAAAUUUCCUUUAGACUAACGAAUAUAUUGGGGGGAGGAAUAGAGGGGAGGUGUGCAGGAACCAGCAAUGAGAAGGCCAGGAAAAGAAAGAGCUGAAAAUGCAGAAAGCCGAAGAGUUAGAACUUUUGGAUACAGCAGAAGAAACAGCGGCUCCACUACCGACCUGCCCCCGGUUCGAUGUCCUUCCAAGAAUGAAGUCUUUCCCUGGUGAUGGUCCCCUGCCCUGUCUUUCCAGCAUCCACUCUGUCUUGUCCUCCUGGAAGUGUAUCUCAGUCAGCCAGUGGCUUCUUGAUGAUGGCGGUGGAGGUGGUGGUUGUAGUGUGAUGGAUCCCCUUUAGGUUAUUUAGGGGUAUAUGUCCCCUGCUUGAACCCUGAAGGCCAGGUAAUGAGCCAUGGCCAUUGUCCCCAGCUGAGGACCAGGUGUCUCUAAAAACCCAAACAUCCUGGAGAGUAUGCGAGAACCUACCAAGAAAAACAGUCUCAUUACUCAUAUACAGCAGGCAAAGAGACAGAAAAUUAACUGAAAAGCAGUUUAGAGACUGGGGGAGGCCGGAUCUCUAGAGCCAUCCUGCUGAGUGCCCUGUGUGUAAGUCCUAAUAAACUCACCUACUCACCAA